ACUCGCAAGCUGGCCAAGGGCUUCACACAAUUUGCCAAGAUGACAGAGGGGACCAAGAAGACCAGCAAAAAGUUCAAGUUCUUCAAGUUCAAGGGCUUUGGGAGUCUCUCCAACCUCCCUCGGUCCUUCACUCUGAGACGAUCCUCAGCUUCCAUCAGUAGGCAGUCCCAUUUGGAGCCUGACACCUUUGAAGCCACGCAGGAUGACAUGGUGACGGUGCCCAAGAGUCCCCCAGCCUAUGCCCGCUCCAGUGACAUGUACAGCCACAUGGGCACCAUGCCUCGCCCCAGCAUCAAGAAAGCACAGAACUCACAGGCUGCCCGGCAGGCCCAGGAGGCGGGUCCCAAGCCCAACUUGGUACCCGGAGGUGUACCCGACCCCCCAGGCUUGGAGGCAGCCAAAGAGGUGAUGGUGAAGGCCACUGGCCCUCUAGAGGACACCCCAGCAAUGGAACCCAACCCUUCAGCAGUGGAGGUAGACCCCAUCAGAAAGCCUGAGGUCCCCACAGGAGACGUAGAAGAGGAGAGACCUCCCAGGGACGUGCACUCAGAAAGGGCUGCUGGAGAGCCAGAGGCUGGCAGCGACUAUGUGAAGUUCUCCAAGGAGAAGUACAUCCUGGACUCAUCGCCAGAGAAACUCCACAAGGAAUUGGAGGAGGAGCUCAAACUCAGCAGCACGGAUCUCCGCAGCCAUGCCUGGUACCAUGGCCGCAUCCCCCGAGAGGUCUCGGAGACCUUGGUACAACGCAACGGCGACUUCCUCAUCCGGGACUCACUCACCAGCCUGGGCGACUAUGUGCUCACGUGCCGCUGGCGCAACCAGGCCUUGCACUUCAAGAUCAACAAGGUGGUGGUGAAGGCAGGCGAGAGCUACACACACAUCCAGUACCUGUUUGAGCAGGAGAGCUUUGACCACGUGCCCGCCCUCGUGCGCUAUCAUGUGGGCAGCCGCAAGGCUGUGUCAGAGCAGAGUGGUGCCAUCAUCUACUGCCCGGUGAACCGCACCUUCCCACUGCGCUACCUCGAGGCCAGCUAUGGCCUGGGACAGGGGAGUAGCAAGCCUGCUAGCCCCGUCAGCCCCUCAGGCCCCAAGGGCAGCCACAUGAAGCGGCGCAGCGUCACCAUGACCGAUGGGCUCACUGCUGACAAGGUCACCCGCAGCGAUGGCUGCCCCACCAGUACGUCGCUGCCCCGCCCUCGGGACUCCAUCCGCAGCUGUGCCCUCAGCAUGGACCAGAUCCCAGACCUGCACUCACCCAUGUCGCCCAUCUCCGAGAGCCCUAGCUCCCCUGCCUACAGCACUGUAACCCGUGUCCAUGCCGCCCCUGCAGCCCCUUCUGCCACAGCAUUGCCUGCCUCCCCUGUCGCCCGCCGUUCCAGUGAGCCCCAGCUGUGUCCCGGAAGUGCCCCAAAGACCCAUGGGGAGUCAGACAAGGGCCCCCACACCAGCCCCUCCCACACCCUUGGCAAGGCCUCCCCGUCACCAUCACUCAGCAGCUACAGUGACCCGGACUCUGGCCACUACUGCCAGCUCCAGCCUCCCGUGCGUGGCAGCCGAGAGUGGGCAGCGACUGAGACCUCCAGCCAGCAGGCCAGGAGCUAUGGGGAGAGGCUAAAGGAACUGUCAGAAAAUGGGGCCCCUGAAGGGGACUGGGGCAAGACCUUCACAGUCCCCAUCGUGGAAGUCACUUCUUCCUUCAACCCGGCCACCUUCCAGUCACUACUGAUCCCCAGGGAUAACCGGCCACUGGAGGUGGGCCUUCUGCGCAAGGUCAAGGAGCUGCUGGCAGAAGUGGAUGCCCGGACGCUGGCCCGGCAUGUCACCAAGGUGGACUGCCUGGUUGCUAGGAUACUGGGCGUUACCAAGGAGAUGCAGACCCUAAUGGGAGUCCGCUGGGGCAUGGAACUGCUCACCCUCCCCCAUGGCCGGCAGCUACGCCUAGACCUGCUGGAAAGGUUCCACACCAUGUCCAUCAUGCUGGCCGUGGACAUCCUGGGCUGCACCGGCUCUGCGGAGGAGCGGGCAGCGCUGCUGCACAAGACCAUUCAGCUGGCGGCCGAGCUGCGGGGGACUAUGGGCAACAUGUUCAGCUUCGCGGCGGUCAUGGGUGCCCUGGACAUGGCCCAGAUUUCUCGGCUGGAGCAGACAUGGGUGACCCUGCGGCAGCGACACACAGAGGGUGCCAUCCUGUACGAGAAGAAGCUCAAGCCUUUUCUCAAGAGCCUCAACGAGGGCAAAGAAGGCCCGCCGCUGAGCAACACCACGUUUCCUCAUGUGCUGCCCCUCAUCACCCUGCUGGAGUGUGACUCGGCCCCACCAGAGGGCCCUGAGCCCUGGGGCAGCACGGAGCACGGCGUGGAGGUGGUGCUGGCUCACCUGGAGGCCGCCCGCACAGUGGCACACCACGGAGGCCUGUACCACACCAAUGCUGAAGUCAAGCUGCAGGGGUUCCAGGCCCGGCCGGAGCUCCUGGAGGUGUUCAGCACGGAGUUCCAGAUGCGCCUUCUCUGGGGCAGUCAGGGUGCCAGCAGCAGCCAGGCCCGGCGCUAUGAGAAGUUCGACAAGGUCCUCACUGCCCUGUCCCACAAGCUGGAACCUGCUGUCCGCUCCAGCGAGCUGUGACCCCAGGGACAUUUCCCCUCUGCAGCUGCGGACAGCGUCAGGGGCAGAGGGGCACACAACUUUCCCCAGAGCACCCCAAGGACACUGUGAUCAACCCGAGAAUGUUCUGGGUUCAACUCAAGCAUCUCCCUUGCACCUCCAGGGUCCUGCGUGGACUCUGGGUUCCAUCCCACCUGCUACAUGCUCACCAGGUCUCCAUUGAGGAAGAACAGGAACGCCGGUUCCCCCACCAGCUUUUGCUGCUCCCCUUCCUGCUGGGGUUCCCUGUUUUCGAGCCAUGGGAGGCAGGCUGCUCACGCCUCCUCACUCUCUGUCUGUCCCUCACCAACACCAAGGCCUCCAUCUCACUGUAAAUAAGUCUCUGUUCUGUAAAUAGAUGUACAGAAGCCAUGUUAUUUCUUUCAUAUAAUAAACUUUUAUGACUCUUUA